UUUACCUUUCCAAGUGGCAUAGCUCCAGGGAAGAUAUUUGGUUGUUGGAAACUUUCAGUGACCACAUAGGAUUUUUAACUAAAUAGAGCAUGAGACCAGAGGCACAAAGCAGUAUCCACAACACUAAGAUUAAGCAAACAUUUGUACUCAAACCAUCAGAAAGAUUCAGUCCCAUAUAUAUGUCACACUGGCUGUGAUUCUCCACUACAAAGGGGAAAUUAUGGAGAUGAGAAAUACUACCCCAGAUUUUAUUCUCCUAGGACUCUUUAACCACACCAGAGCCCACCAAGUCCUCUUCAUGAUGGUUCUGAGUAUCGUUUUGACCUCCCUGUUUGGCAAUUCCCUCAUGAUUCUCCUGAUUCACUGGGACCACCGGCUCCACACGCCCAUGUACUUCCUCCUGAGCCAACUUUCCCUCAUGGACAUGAUGCUGGUUUCCACCACUGUGCCCAAAAUGGCGGCUGACUACUUGACCGGAAGUAAGGCCAUCUCCCGCGCUGGCUGUGGUGUGCAGAUCUUCUUCCUCCCCACACUGGGUGGUGGAGAGUGCUUCCUCUUAGCAGCCAUGGCCUAUGACCGCUAUGCGGCUGUCUGCCACCCACUCCGAUAUCCCACUCUCAUGAGCUGGCAGCUGUGCCUGAGGAUGACCAUGUCGUGUUGGCUCCUGGGUGCAGCUGACGGGCUCCUGCAGGCUGUUGUUACCCUGAGCUUCCCAUAUUGUGGUGCACACGAGAUCGAUCACUUCUUCUGCGAGACCCCCGUGCUGGUGCGUUUGGCUUGUGCUGACACUUCAGUCUUCGAAAACGCCAUGUACAUCUGCUGUGUGUUAAUGCUCCUGGUCCCCUUUUCCCUCAUCCUGUCCUCCUAUGGUCUCAUCCUCGCUGCUGUUCUGCACAUGCGCUCUACAGAAGCCCGCAAGAAGGCCUUUGCCACCUGCUCUUCACAUGUGGCUGUGGUGGGACUCUUUUAUGGAGCUGCCAUUUUUACCUAUAUGAGACCCAAAUCCCAUAGGUCCACUAACCAUGACAAGGUUGUGUCAGCCUUCUAUACUAUGUUCACCCCUUUACUAAACCCCCUCAUCUACAGUGUGAAGAACAGUGAGGUGAAGGGAGCCCUGAAACGGUGGCUGGGGACGUGUGUAAACAUAAAACACCAGCAAAAUGAGGCCCACAGGUCAAGAUGAUCUAAUGUCAAAUGAGUCUAAGUUCCUGAAUUUAUUAAUAUUUUAACACAUUGUUAUUCUCUCCCUUUAGCAAUUCAUGCAGAGAAAAUUAAGUUUUUGCAUUGAUAUAAUAGGAUAUUUUUAAGAAUUAAGUGAGCUAAUUGUAUUGAGAGAUACCAUUUUUAGCAUUUAUGUACUUUUCUUCAAGUGAAGUAGUAUCUAUGGAUUACUUUGUAUCCUACAACAACCCCAUGAUAUAAGUACUGUUGACAAUAUCUCCUACUUUCUAAAAAAAGAAAUUAAUGCAUGGAAAGGUAAAUAUUGUUCCCAAUUUCACACAGCACGGAAAUAAUAAGAAGUGACUCCAGAGCUUGUUCCUUAACCUGGAAUAGUUUAUUUCUGUUCAAUAAUGUAUUUUGAGUGUUAUUUCAUAGGUGUAUGCUCUACAAUUAAAAACUAAAUAUGAGGACUCCACCAAAGAAAAAUAUUAUUUUUAUGUUAUAUUUUAAAAUAUAGAUGCAUGACAAAAGGGAAAGUCCACAACUCAAAUGUAACUGCUAUAUUGCCACAAUUUUUUUGUAUUUUUUCAACAGUCUAUUUGGUGUUUAAACGUAAGCCUUUUUUAAUUUAUGUAACCUUUCAUUUAAGUAUUUUUUUUUCCAGGGCCUCAUUGUAAUUGAAUUGGAAAAUUGUUUUAAACUACAACUAAGUUCUGUUUUCUACACCUGCUUUAAGGUUACCUUGACUUAUUGACAUACCUCCAUCGAUAUGAACUCUGAAUUGCAUAAUCAUGCUGAAUCUUGACAGUUACUAACAAUGAAUUAUCAAAACUGAGUAACACUCAACAACCUUAUACAUUAUUGUGUCACCACCUUACUUCUGCCAAGACAUAGGUAAUUAGAGGUAUUUCUGUUGAAAAAUUUGGGACACCUUCUAAAGAUCUGGGGUUUGCAAAACAAAAAAAAAGAAGACUAUUCUAUUAAUAAAGACACAAGCUAGAUAGUGAUGGCAGAAAGCUGUGGUUAUCAAAGCCAAAUUGUAACCAGAGACUGGAUAUCAAAUCGUCUUAGAGAGUUUUAUGAUAAAGGCUAUAUUUCCUGUAUGUAAAACACACUUAAGAAAUAAUAUAAGUUUUAAACACACAGUGGGACAUAACUAAGAGCUUCCAGGGACAGUGUAUCUUCAAUAUAAGUGUCUGAAAGUUAACCUGCCAUUUCUGGCCAUCCUGAAUUUCAAAAGGGACUUGUUUUAGAACAAAUGAAAGGAGUUUUCUGCUUCAUCUAGAGCUUCAGGUUCCAAAGCAGUAAUAUAUUUAAGAUAGUACCUUAACCAGUGCAUGCAGAUCCUGAGCCUAUGUCUCAAGAGAAGGUUAUUCAGUAACUCUUUUCUCCUUGGAAGACUUGAGGAUGAAAGGAGAGAGUGUCAUCUGUUUGAUACUUUUGUUUGCUACUCUUGUUAAUUUUAUCUCCUUACCCAGUGUUAGGGUGAGAAAGGAGCAGAACUGCACAAAUUCUGUCAUUUAUACCAUCUAAAAAAAUCUUCUCUUAGAAUGGGUGAAAUUUACACAAGUAAAUGUAGUCAUGGAAAUUUCAUUACUCAUACCAGGUUCAUUCACCAUCAGAGAAAUUAUUUUAGAACAUGUUGAGCUAAAAAUGGUAAACUAAGCCUAUAAAAUUUUGUAAGGAUAAAAUAUUCUAACCAGAAAAUUAAGCCUAAUAUACAGGAGAAAACUAAAACAACUAGCAUUUGGCAUUUGAAUAUUUUUAAUUUUAACCCUUCUAGUGGUGGUAUCUUUAUGUCAUUUUAAAAUAUGCCAUUACCUAGAGAAUAAUGAAGUUCAGUGCCUUCUUAGAUGCUGACCAGUCAUUGAUAUAUGUAAUUUUAAGAAGAGUAUCUUUAUAUCUUUGGCCAAAAUGUUUUUGUUUUUAUUUAUUUUACUCAGUUUUAAAUUUUUUAUUUAUUCUGGACAAAAGUAUUUUGUCAAACAUCUGUACUAUAAAUAUUUUUUCCUGCUUUUUGGCUAGCCUGUUUGUUAUUUUAAUGGUAUAUUUUUCAGAGCAGAGAUUUUGAUUUUUGUAAAGUCCAAUAUAUAAUUUUGUUUUCUACGAUUAGUGGGUGUUUCUUAUGUAUUAUCUCUAUAAAAAUUAUAUACUUCAAGAAUGAAAGGAUGGCAUCUAUUUUUUUAACAUGAAAUUAGCAUUUUAAUGUGAACAACUCAGUGGCAUUUACUACAUUCGCAAUGUUGUACGACCAUCAUCACUAACUCCAAAACACUUCCAUCACUCCAAAGUAAAACCCCUCAUCCAUUAAGCAGUUUUUCUCCCCAUUUCAGCCCCUAGCAACUGCCAAUCUGCAUUUGGUCUCUCUGGAUUUAUCUACUGUAGAUAUUUUAUGUAAACGGAAUCAUAAAAGAUAUGAGCUUUUAUGUCUGGCUUCUUUCACUUUUUCUUUAAAAUUAUUCUUUAAGUUCUAGGGUACAUGUGCACAACGUGCAGGUUUGUUACAUAUGCAUACAUGUGUCAUGUUGGUGUGCUGCACUCAUUAACUCAUCAUUUACAUUAGGUAUAUCUCCUAGUGCUAUCCCUCCCCGCUUCCCCCACCCCACAACAGGCCCCGGUGUGUGAUGUUCCCCUUUCUGUGUCCAAGUGUUCUCAUUGUUCAAUUCCCACCUAUGAGUGAGAACAUGCUGUGUUUGGUUUUUUGUCCUUGCGAUAGUUUGCUGAGAAUGAUGGUUUCCAGCUUCAUCCGUGUCCCUACAAAGGACGUGAACUCAUCCUUUUUUAUGGCUGCAUAGUAUUCCAUGGUAUAUAUGUGCCACAUUAUCUUAAUCCAGUCCAUCAUUGCUGGAAAUUUGUGUUGGUUCCAAGUCUUUGCUGUUGUGAAUACUGCCUCAAUAAACAUAUGUGUGCAUGUGUCUUUAUAGCAGCAUGAUUUAUAAUCCUUGGGUAUAUAGGUG